AGUCCCAGGCAUCUGACUACCGGGAACCUCAGCCAGAGUCCGGGAGCCCCCCACCCCGUCCAGGAGCCAACAGAGCCCCCGUCUUGCUGGCGUGAGAAUACAUUGCUCUCCUUUGGUUGAAUCAGCUGUCCCUCUUCGUGGGAAAAUGAACCAGAAGACAAUCCUCGUGCUCCUCAUUCUGGCCGUCAUCACCAUCUUUGCCUUGGUUUGUGUCCUGCUGGUGGGCAGGGGUGGAGAUGGGGGUGAACCCAGCCAGCUUCCCCAUUGCCCCUCUGUAUCUCCCAGUGCCCAGCCUUGGACACACCCUGGCCAGAGCCAGCUGUUUGCAGACCUGAGCCGAGAGGAGCUGACGGCUGUGAUGCGCUUUCUGACCCAGCGGCUGGGGCCAGGGCUGGUGGAUGCAGCCCAGGCCCGGCCCUCGGACAACUGUGUCUUCUCAGUGGAGUUGCAGCUGCCUCCCAAGGCUGCAGCCCUGGCUCACUUGGACAGGGGGAGCCCCCCACCUGCCCGGGAGGCACUGGCCAUCGUCUUCUUUGGCAGGCAACCCCAGCCCAACGUGAGUGAGCUGGUGGUGGGGCCACUGCCUCACCCCUCCUACAUGCGGGACGUGACUGUGGAGCGUCAUGGAGGCCCCCUGCCCUAUCACCGACGCCCCGUGCUGUUCCAAGAGUACCUGGACAUAGACCAGAUGAUCUUCAACAGAGAGCUGCCCCAGGCUUCUGGGCUUCUCCACCACUGUUGCUUCUACAAGCACCGGGGACGGAACCUGGUGACAAUGACCACGGCUCCCCGUGGUCUGCAAUCAGGGGACCGGGCCACCUGGUUUGGCCUCUACUACAACAUCUCGGGCGCUGGGUUCUUCCUGCACCACGUGGGCUUGGAGCUGCUAGUGAACCACAAGGCCCUUGACCCUGCCCGCUGGACUAUCCAGAAGGUGUUCUAUCAAGGCCGCUACUACGACAGCCUGGCCCAGCUGGAGGCCCAGUUUGAGGCCGGCCUGGUGAAUGUGGUGCUGAUCCCAGACAAUGGCACAGGUGGGUCCUGGUCCCUGAAGUCCCCUGUGCCCCCGGGUCCAGCUCCCCCUCUACAGUUCUAUCCCCAAGGCCCCCGCUUCAGUGUCCAGGGAAGUCGAGUGGCCUCCUCACUGUGGACUUUCUCCUUUGGCCUCGGAGCAUUCAGUGGCCCAAGGAUCUUUGACGUUCGCUUCCAAGGAGAAAGACUAGUUUAUGAGAUAAGCCUCCAAGAGGCCUUGGCCAUCUAUGGUGGAAAUUCCCCAGCAGCAAUGACGACCCGCUAUGUGGAUGGAGGCUUUGGCAUGGGCAAGUACACCACGCCCCUGACCCGUGGGGUGGACUGCCCCUACUUGGCCACCUACGUGGACUGGCACUUCCUUUUGGAGUCCCAGGCCCCCAAGACAAUACGUGAUGCCUUUUGUGUGUUUGAACAGAACCAGGGCCUCCCCCUGCGGCGACACCACUCAGAUCUCUACUCGCACUACUUUGGGGGUCUUGCGGAAACGGUGCUGGUCGUCAGAUCUAUGUCCACCUUGCUCAACUAUGACUAUGUGUGGGAUACGGUCUUCCACCCCAGUGGGGCCAUAGAAAUACGAUUCUAUGCCACGGGCUACAUCAGCUCGGCAUUCCUCUUUGGUGCUACUGGGAAGUACGGGAACCAAGUGUCAGAGCACACCCUGGGCACGGUCCACACCCACAGCGCCCACUUCAAGGUGGAUCUGGAUGUAGCAGCCUUCUGUUUGUCAGCUCAGUUCUGUGUCUGGCCUGUGGUGGUGGUGUUUUGGAGGAUCUCUUUGCAUUCUACCACGUCCCUGGCAUGUGCAGGACUGGAGAACUGGGUCUGGGCCGAGGAUAUGGUCUUUGUCCCCAUGGCUGUGCCCUGGAGCCCUGAGCACCAGCUGCAGAGGCUGCAGGUGACCCGGAAGCUGCUGGAGAUGGAGGAGCAGGCCGCCUUCCUCGUGGGAAGCGCCACCCCUCGCUACCUGUACCUGGCCAGCAACCACAGCAACAAGUGGGGUCACCCCCGGGGCUACCGCAUCCAGAUGCUCAGCUUUGCUGGAGAGCCGCUGCCCCAAAACAGCUCCAUGGCGAGAGGCUUCAGCUGGGAGAGGUACCAGCUGGCUGUGACCCAGCGGAAGGAGGAGGAGCCCAGUAGCAGCAGCGUUUUCAAUCAGAAUGACCCUUGGGCCCCCACUGUGGAUUUCAGUGACUUCAUCAACAAUGAGACCAUUGCUGGAAAGGAUUUGGUGGCCUGGGUGACAGCUGGUUUUCUGCAUAUCCCACAUGCAGAGGACAUUCCUAACACAGUGACUGUGGGGAACGGCGUGGGCUUCUUCCUCCGACCCUAUAACUUCUUUGACGAAGACCCCUCCUUCUACUCUGCCGACUCCAUCUACUUCCGAGGGGACCAGGAUGCUGGGGCCUGCGAGGUCAACCCCCUAGCUUGCCUGCCCCAGGCUGCUGCCUGUGCCCCCGACCUCCCUGCCUUCUCCCACGGGGGCUUCUCUCACAACUAGGCGGUCCUGGGAUGGGGCAUGUGGCCAAGGGCUCCAGGGCCAGGGUGUGAGGGAUGGGGAGCAGCUGGGCACUGGGCCGGCAGCCUGGUUCCCUCUUUCCUGUGCCAGGACUCUCUUUCUUCCACUACCCUCCCUCGCAUCCGCCUCUGAGCCAGGAGCCUCCUGACCCUGUGAUGCCUGACACAGGGGACACUGAACCUUGUUGAUGCCAGCUGUACUGAGUUCUCAUCCACAGAGGCCAGGCAUGGCCCAGCCUGGAGCCGUGGCCGAGGGCUUCCCUAGAUGGUUCCCUUUGUUGCUGUCUGGCUUUCCCGAAUCUUUUUAGGCCACCUCCAAGGACUCUAAAAGGGGGCUAUUCCCUGGAGACCCCAGAGUAGGGUUGCCAGUCCUGCAAGUCCAUAGCUGAGCUGGAAAGGAUGCUUCUGCUCACAUUCCCUCUCAUCCAGGUCCUUUCCUUCUCGUCUUCCUCUCUCUCACCUACUUCCUCCUCCUCCUCCUGUUCCUGCCUUCUCUUCUAUCCUGCAAUUUCUCCCGAAUCCUGAGGGGAUAUCCCUAUGUCCCAGCCCCUGGUACUCCCCCAGCCCUCAGUUUUCAGUCAAGUUCCGUCUCCUCUCCAGCCCUAUGGAAGUCUCAAGGUCACGGGACCCCUAAUCAGAGUGGCCAAUCCCUGUGUGUCGUUCCCUUGUGUCUGUUGCUUAUUGGGAGUAGGAGUUGCUCCUACCCCUGUCCUGGGGCUGGGUGUGUUUCAGGACAGCUGCUUCUGUGCAUUUGUGUCUGCCUGCCUCAUGCUCUCUAUAGAGGAGGAUGGUCAUCGUGACAGCAGCAGCUCAAGUUAGCAUUUCAAGUGAUUUGGGGGUGCAAUGAUAAUGAAGAAUGGCCAUUUUGUACCAGGGCUCUGUAUUCUGCAACAGCCUGUUUGGGAGGCUGGAGUGGAAACAAAGGGUGGGCAUCAAAGAUGAGAAGCCAAAGCCCCUACAACUCCAGCCACCCAGCCAGGAGGGGCUGUCCAAUCACAUUCAGGCAUGCGAAUGAGCUGGGCCCUGGGUGAGGUGGGGGUCUGGCCUAGUGGGGAGGGGCCUGGCCUGGGUGGGGCAGGGCCUGGCCUGGUCCAGGCUUGGGCUCCAUUCCCAUCACUGCUGUCCCUCCUGAGGUCUGGAUUGGGGAUGGGGACAAAGAAAUAGCAAGAGAUGAGAAACAACAGAAACUUUUUUCUCUAAAGGACUGGUUAAAUCAAUUCUGAUACAGCCUUACAAUACAAUAGUAUGCAGCUAAAAAAUAAUUGUAUGUCUUUAUAUACUAAUAUGUAAUAAUCUUCAGGUGAAAAAGGCAAGCCACAGAAAUGUGUAUAGCGCACUUCCCAUUUGUGUUUCAGAAAGGAGUAGAAUAUAAACACAUAAUUGCUUAUGUAUGCCUAUUCAGAAUAAAUGGGUAACACUGAUUACUUUUGGGAGGGGAACCAGUAGGUUGAGGACAGGAGAGGGAAGGGUCUUAACACUUACACCCUUUUGUACAUUUUGAAUUUUGAACCAUGUGACUGUAUUACCUAUUCAAAAUAAACAAUAAAUGGGCCCAAA